GCCUUCCUAGUGGAGACGCGAGUGGGGGAGGAGCAGUCCGAGGGGAACGUGGGUUGAACGUUGCAACUAGGGUGGAGAUCAAGCUGGAACAGGAGUUCCGAUCGACCCGGUACCAAGAAGGGGAGUGCCCGCGGCAGGUAAGGGAGAAGAGGGAGGGGUUUCUUUCCGCUCUCGAAAUUGGGAAAAGAGACAGAGCUGGGAUGACCUAUGGGGUAGUCGGCGCGCUGAAAGGAUGGGCUGGGCUGGGACGGGGUUCAAGUGGGAAAGGUUGAUGAUUAAGGUAUAGAGUUGGACUUACAGAUCCGUUUGGGCGCAGAGAGGUGAACGCUGAAGAGAAACCAGAGUUUGUUUUCGUUUUCCAAGGAGCGUGGAGAUGGGCAGGGUUAACGGACCCUGCGCCUCCUUCGGCUUCUUAGUUUGGGUGUUGAAACUCACCUCCUUUGGUCCUGUUCGUCUCUGAUUCAAGACAGUUGGGUUUGGUACCUGACAGGGCUGGGUGCAGAAAGCUGACCCUGUUCCUCGGCUUCCAGGUCGGUUGUGGCCUCGCUUUUGACAGUUCACGUGCCGAGCCUACUCGCUCUCGGAGGGCGAGCUCAAAUGGGUGGGUUUAAGGCCCCCUCUUCGAACAGCUGUUUCCCUGGGUUUCUCCAUUUUGCACACAGGAGUGUGAAUUAAGUUUAAUUGAAUACUUUUUGCGAUUCCCAGGGCCACCUUGACACGUUCAUUGUGCUAUCUAACUGGGUUCAUGCUGGGCUAAUAAUUCACAUUAAGGCUUCUGGAGUAUAAGUGGUUCACAGAAGUAUGAAAAGGGGAUGUUAGAAGAAAGAUGCUGGGGGUGAAGUAGAGUUGAGGAAGACAGAACUGGAAAGCUAGGUUGGUUUCACAGUACAAUGAGCUUUAGGUCAUAAUACUACCUUUAGGUUAUAUUGGGCUGUUUGGACGGAGUUUGCUGUAAUCAGGCUAGAGUAAAUAGAGAAUUUUAAACUAAGCAUUGACAGGCUCAGACUUGUAGAGGCAUCAUUUUGACAGUGAUAUGGAAGGGAAAGAGGUAGAGAUUUGAGACCUUUCCAAAGAACUGUCCACAGAAUUUGGUGACUUACUGUGCGAAGAGGGAAAUAAAGAAUAGGGAACAACUCAAGACUUUCUAGUCUGUGUGUUUGGAAGGAUGGAGACGCCCACAUUUAAGUGAGAUAUGGGAAGGAGGAGCAGAUUGUUUUUGAAGGGAGGAAGAGCAGUUACUUAGGGUCAAAUUAAGUUGUAAAAUCCCCCCCGGGAUUUUGUAUGUAAGUCAAAGUGAAUUGUAUUUGGAAGAAGAACUGGGGAGCCCACCUCUGGUAUUUUUUUUAUGUCCCUCAUAUGGACAAAUAAACCUCUGGUAUUAAAUGAAUUUUCUUUUGGGGGAUUCUAUAUAUUCGGGAUUUCAACCACCAACCUAUCUGGUUUUUCCCGCUGAAAUGUUGGGUGAUGGAAUCAGGAGAGCAGAUUUGGAGACUCUUUAUAUUUUAUAAUUGAGAGAGACAAAGAGAAAACCGUUUGAUUUGAAAAAGUUUUCUAGGUUCCCUCAGGUAGAUGGAAAUUUUCAUCAAAAACAGUUUAUUCAAGGUACAUAGCCUACUAGUUUCCCAUUUGAGAGUACCGCAGAAUGAUACGACGUGUACUGCUUCUCUACGCAGAAUGAAGUAUAAAAUUAGCACCAAAUAGUAACUUUAAUUUGUCAGGUGCUAAACUUUUUACAUGCUUUAUCUCAUUUAAUUCUUAGAAGAAACUAAUUUUACAAGUAAGUGUCUGGACCAACAUCUGCAGGUACAAAGCCUGAAAAGCGGUUCAUUGAAAAAAUCCUUAGUGAUAUUGACAUGUCUCAAGUGACAUAAAUUAGCCAAUGACUCGGAAUGAUGGAUUCUCCGAAGAUUGGAAAUGGUUUGCCAGUGAUUGGACCAGGGACUGAUAUAGGGAUAUCUUCACUCCACAUGGUGGGGUAUUUGGGAAAAAAUUUUGAUUCAGCUAAAGUUCCAUCAGAUGAGUAUUGCCCUGCUUGUAGAGAGAAGGGAAAGUUAAAAGCCUUAAAGACUUACCGAAUUAGUUUUCAAGAAUCUAUCUUUUUGUGUGAGGAUCUGCAGUGCAUCUAUCCUUUGGGCUCUAAAUCACUUAAUAACCUAAUUUCUCCUGAUUUGGAAGAAUGUCACACUCCACAUAAGCCUCAGAAAAGGAAGAGCUUAGAAAGCAGCUAUAAGGAUUCACUUCUUUUAGCAAAUUCCAAAAAGACUAGAAAUUAUAUUGCUAUUGACGGUGGAAAAGUUUUGAACAGCAAACAUAAUGGAGAAGUAUAUGACGAAACCUCGUCAAACUUACCUGAUAGUAGUGGUCAACAGAAUCCAAUUAGGACAGCUGAUUCCUUGGAGCGGAAUGAGAUUUUGGAAGCUGAUACUGUUGACAUGGCUACUACAAAAGAUCCUGCUACAGUUGAUGUCUCUGGAACUGGCAGACCUUCCCCUCAAAAUGAAGGAUGUACAUCUAAACUGGAAAUGCCACUGGAGAGCAAAUGUACAUCAUUUCCCCAGGCUUUAUGUGUCCAGUGGAAAAAUGCUUAUGCUCUCUGUUGGUUAGACUGUAUCCUGUCAGCUUUGGUGCACUCGGAAGAGUUAAAGAACACCGUGACUGGACUGUGCUCGAAGGAGGAAUCUAUAUUCUGGCGGUUGCUUACAAAAUAUAAUCAAGCAAAUACACUUCUAUAUACCAGUCAAUUGAGUGGUGUUAAAGAUGGAGAUUGUAAAAAACUUACCUCAGAAAUAUUUGCAGAGAUAGAGACCUGUCUGAAUGAAGUUAGAGAUGAAAUUUUUAUUAGCCUUCAGCCCCAGCUUAGAUGCACAUUAGGUGAUAUGGAAAGCCCUGUGUUUGCAUUUCCCCUGCUCUUAAAACUAGAAACCCACAUUGAAAAGCUCUUCCUAUAUUCUUUUUCUUGGGACUUUGAAUGUUCGCAGUGUGGACACCAAUAUCAAAACAGGCAUAUGAAGAGUCUGGUCACCUUUACAAAUGUCAUCCCUGAGUGGCACCCACUUAAUGCUGCCCAUUUUGGUCCAUGUAACAAUUGCAACAGUAAAUCACAAAUAAGAAAAAUGGUAUUAGAAAAAGUAUCUCCCAUAUUCAUGUUGCACUUUGUAGAAGGCUUACCACAGAAUGACUUGCAGCACUAUGCAUUUCAUUUUGAAGGCUGUCUUUAUCAGAUAACUUCUGUAAUUCAGUAUCGAGCAAAUAAUCAUUUUAUAACAUGGAUUUUAGAUGCUGAUGGAAGUUGGCUGGAAUGUGAUGACUUAAAAGGCCCAUGUUCUGAAAGGCACAAGAAAUUUGAAGUUCCUGCUUCAGAGAUACAUAUUGUUAUUUGGGAAAGAAAAAUAUCCCAAGUGACAGAUAAAGAAGCUGCCUGCCUUCCACUUAAAAAGACUAAUGACCAACACGCUCUCAGUAAUGAGAAACCAGUAUCUUUAACAUCGUGUUCUGUGGGUGAUGCUGCCUCAGCUGAAACAGCCUCAGUAACUCACCCUAAAGAUAUAUCAGUUGCCCCUCGUACUCUUUCACAGGACACAGCUGUAACUCAUGGAGAUCAUUUACUUUCAGGUCCAAAAGGUUUGGUUGACAAUAUUUUACCUCUGACACUUGAAGAAACUAUCCAGAAAACAGCCUCAGUUUCACAGUUAAAUUCUGAAGCUUUCCUGUUAGAAAAUAAACCUGUAGCAGAAAAUACAGGAAUUCUCAAAACCAAUACUUUGCUAUCACAAGAAUCACUAAUGGCUUCUUCAGUAUCAGCUCCAUGUAAUGAAAAGCUUAUUCAAGACCAAUUUGUGGACAUAAGUUUUCCAUCCCAAGUUGUAAAUACAAACAUGCAGUCAGUACAGCUGAAUACAGAAGAUACUGUAAAUACUAAAUCUGUGAAUAAUACUGAUGCUACUGGUCUUAUACAGGGAGUGAAGUCAGUAGAAAUUGAGAAGGACGCUCAGUUAAAACAAUUCCUUACACCAAAAACUGAACAAUUAAAACCAGAACGUGUCACAUCUCAGGUAUCUAAUUUGAAGAAAAAAGAAACUACAGCAGAUUCUCAAACCACAACAUCUAAGUCAUUACAGAAUCAGUCUCUGAAAGAAAAUCAGAAGAAGCCAUUUGUGGGAAGUUGGGUUAAAGGCUUAAUAAGCAGGGGUGCUUCUUUUAUGCCACUCUGUGUUUCAGCUCAUAAUAGAAACACUAUAACUGAUUUACAACCUUCAGUUAAAGGGGUAAAUAAUUUUGGUGGCUUUAAAACUAAAGGUAUAAACCAGAAGGCCAGCCACGUAUCCAAGAAAGCUCGUAAGAGUGCAAGUAAGCCUCCUCCCAUCAGUAAGCCACCAGCAGGCCCUCCAUCGUCUAAUGGCACAGCUGCCCACCCACAUGCUCAUGCUGCUUCAGAAGUUUUGGAAAAGUCUGGAAGCACCUCAUGUGGAGCUCAACUCAACCACAGUUCUUAUGGGAAUGGUAUUUCUUCAGCAAACCAUGAAGACUUGGUGGAAGGUCAGAUUCAUAAACUUCGUCUAAAACUUCGUAAAAAGCUAAAGGCAGAAAAGAAGAAAUUAGCUGCUCUUAUGUCUUCCCCGCAAAGCAGAACAGUUCGAAGUGAAAAUCUAGAACAGGUGCCCCAGGAUGGGUCUCCAAAUGAUUGUGAAUCAAUAGAGGACUUGUUAAAUGAGCUACCAUAUCCAAUUGAUAUUGCCAGUGAGUCUGCAUGCACCACUGUUCCUGGUGUUUCCCUGUACAGUAGUCAAACUCAUGAAGAAAUUUUAGCGGAAUUAUUGUCUCCUACACCUGUUUCAACAGAGCUGUCAGAAAAUGGGGAAGGUGACUUUAGGUAUUUGGGAAUGGGAGAUAGUCAUAUCCCACCACCAGUACCAAGUGAAUUCAAUGAUGUUUCCCAGAACACACAUCUGAGACAGGACCAUAAUUAUUGUAGCCCCACCAAGAAAAAUCCAUGUGAAGUUCAGCCAGACUCUCUGACAAAUAAUGCCUGCGUUAGAACAUUAAACUUGGAGAGUCCGAUGAAGACUGAUAUUUUCGAUGAGUUUUUUUCCUCCUCAGCAUUAAAUGCUUUAGCAAAUGACACAUUAGACCUACCUCAUUUCGAUGAAUAUCUGUUUGAGAAUUAUUGAAUUAAUGCUUGUUAACUUUUUUCAUAUAAUAUUUAUUAUUAUUAGAAGAACUUACAAUGUGUUCAGGUAGUGUUUAUACACUGGACUUGUGUAAUUACUUGUGUAAUAACCAUGAACAAAAUGCAAGGUUUAACCUUUGGUUCUGCCCAUGAAGCAUGUAAUCUUUCUUACACAUUAAAAUCACUGAAUGUGUUCUCCUUUUUGGUUUCAUUUUGUUCUUGUGAGAGUAUGAGGAUUUCAAAAUGUUAAAGAUGAAAAGUGGCGUCUAGUUUCUGACAGUUUGUACAGUUGGAUGCAUUACAUUUUUAGAUUUGAAGUUUUGGUUAUGUUAGUGUUAUGAGUGAUCUUUGUGGUGGUUUUCUUCCCCUGGAAACCUGUUGCUCGUGGCGCUUUGCCCACGGUGCCCGAGUUCUUGUCCUGUGUCCAGAUAUGCAGACAAAUGAAGGGUGAAGAAGAAGAAGAGGAGCUUUAUUUAGUGUUAGAACAGCUCAGAAGGAGACCCACAGUGAGCAGCUCCCCUGUGUCGGCGGGCAGGUCGUCCCUCAAGUGUUCAGCUCUCAGCAGAGAAAAGGCCCUGGAGAGGGUGACUCCUCUCAGCUCUCAGCAGAGAAGCAGCCCUGGAGAAGGUAGCUUCUGUUCGCAGGCAGAUUGUCCAGAGGUCCUGCUGCUCUCAGACGGGGCCCUGGAGAGGAUAGCUUCUAUCCAUAGGCAGGUUGUUCUGCCGUCUCUACAGGUCUCUGAAGCUCUUAGCAGAGAGGGUAGCUCCUCCCUGUUGCUGGUCGUCCCACCCUCUGCUCAGUUCUGGCUGAGCCUGGGGCAUUUUACGGGCCUCGGGGGAGGAAGUGCAUACUUACUGGCCUGGAAAAGGCACCAGUUCCCACUCCUACAGGUGGGACUGGCAGCCUGGCCCUCAGCCUUCAGGCCCUCCCUGUUCAUGGCUUCCAGGCUUACCCCCCUGCUUUGAUCUGAGAGCUGGUGCCAAUAGCAGGGAGAAGCCAAGCUGCAGAGGCAAGCACUUCCGAGCCUGCAAAAGCAGGCCCCCAAAAGUGCAGGGAUGCCUGAGUCUGCACCCGCACCCAGGAGGGUGGAGAUCUUGCCUGCUCCAAGGCUGCAGCCGGAAUGAUAGCAGGCUGACUGGAGCACCUGCCACCAUCAUUAGUUCAAGAGUUUAUGCAGAUUUAAGUUGUAUACGGUAUAUGAAUGUGUGACAGUUUUCCUUAUGGUUGUGUGGCCUUCUGUAAGAGCCUACGCCUGUUUGUUACACCGGUAGAGUGCUGUGGAAUGUAAACUUUCCCUAUGUCACUUAUCUCCUUUAUCUCUCCAUACAGAGGAGGGCAAGAAACCUUGUUACUUGAACUUUAGUAAUGUUAAGUGAUCAAUAAAUCUAUAAAUAAAUGAUAGCAGAAAAAA